AGAUGCUGCCAGGGUCCCUGAAGAGGGAAGACACGCGGAAACAGGCUUGCACCCAGACACGACACCAUGCAUCUCCUCGGCCCCUGGCUCCUGCUCCUGGUUCUAGAAUACUUGGCUUUCUCUGACUCAAGUAAAUGGGUUUUUGAGCACCCUGAAACCCUCUACGCCUGGGAGGGGGCCUGCGUCUGGAUCCCCUGCACCUACAGAGCCCUAGAUGGUGACCUGGAAAGCUUCAUCCUGUUCCACAAUCCUGAGUAUAACAAGAACACCUCGAAGUUUGAUGGGACAAGACUCUAUGAAAGCACAAAGGAUGGGAAGGUUCCUUCUGAGCAGAAAAGGGUGCAAUUCCUGGGAGACAAGAAUAAGAACUGCACACUGAGUAUCCACCCGGUGCACCUCAAUGACAGUGGUCAGCUGGGGCUGAGGAUGGAGUCCAAGACUGAGAAAUGGAUGGAACGAAUACACCUCAAUGUCUCUGAAAGGCCUUUUCCACCUCAUAUCCAGCUCCCUCCAGAAAUUCAAGAGUCCCAGGAAGUCACUCUGACCUGCUUGCUGAAUUUCUCCUGCUAUGGGUAUCCGAUCCAAUUGCAGUGGCUCCUAGAGGGGGUUCCAAUGAGGCAGGCUGCUGUCACCUCGACCUCCUUGACCAUCAAGUCUGUCUUCACCCGGAGCGAGCUCAAGUUCUCCCCACAGUGGAGUCACCAUGGGAAGAUUGUGACCUGCCAGCUUCAGGAUGCAGAUGGGAAGUUCCUCUCCAAUGACACGGUGCAGCUGAACGUGAAGCACACCCCGAAGUUGGAGAUCAAGGUCACUCCCAGUGAUGCCAUAGUGAGGGAGGGGGACUCUGUGACCAUGACCUGCGAGGUCAGCAGCAGCAACCCGGAGUACACGACGGUAUCCUGGCUCAAGGAUGGGACCUCGCUGAAGAAGCAGAAUACAUUCACGCUAAACCUGCGCGAAGUGACCAAGGACCAGAGUGGGAAGUACUGCUGUCAGGUCUCCAAUGACGUGGGCCCGGGAAGGUCGGAAGAAGUGUUCCUGCAAGUGCAGUAUGCCCCGGAACCUUCCACGGUUCAGAUCCUCCACUCACCGGCUGUGGAGGGAAGUCAAGUCGAGUUUCUUUGCAUGUCACUGGCCAAUCCUCUUCCAACAAAUUACACGUGGUACCACAAUGGGAAAGAAAUGCAGGGAAGGACAGAGGAGAAAGUCCACAUCCCAAAGAUCCUCCCCUGGCACGCUGGGACUUAUUCCUGUGUGGCAGAAAACAUUCUUGGUACUGGACAGAGGGGCCCGGGAGCUGAGCUGGAUGUCCAGUAUCCUCCCAAGAAGGUGACCACAGUGAUUCAAAACCCCAUGCCGAUUCGAGAAGGAGACACAGUGACCCUUUCCUGUAACUACAAUUCCAGUAACCCCAGUGUUACCCGGUAUGAAUGGAAACCCCAUGGCGCCUGGGAGGAGCCAUCGCUUGGGGUGCUGAAGAUCCAAAACGUUGGCUGGGACAACACAACCAUCGCCUGCGCAGCUUGUAAUAGUUGGUGCUCGUGGGCCUCCCCUGUCGCCCUGAAUGUCCAGUAUGCCCCCCGAGACGUGAGGGUCCGGAAAAUCAAGCCCCUUUCCGAGAUUCACUCUGGAAACUCGGUCAGCCUCCAAUGUGACUUCUCAAGCAGCCACCCCAAAGAAGUCCAGUUCUUCUGGGAGAAAAAUGGCAGGCUUCUGGGGAAAGAAAGCCAGCUGAAUUUUGACUCCAUCUCCCCAGAAGAUGCUGGGAGUUACAGCUGCUGGGUGAACAACUCCAUAGGACAGACAGCGUCCAAGGCCUGGACACUUGAAGUGCUGUAUGCACCCAGGAGGCUGCGUGUGUCCAUGAGCCCGGGGGACCAAGUGAUGGAGGGGAAGAGUGCAACCCUGACCUGUGAGAGCGACGCCAACCCUCCCGUCUCCCACUACACCUGGUUUGACUGGAAUAACCAAAGCCUCCCCUACCACAGCCAGAAGCUGAGAUUGGAGCCGGUGAAGGUCCAGCACUCGGGUGCCUACUGGUGCCAGGGGACCAACAGUGUGGGCAAGGGCCGUUCGCCUCUCAGCACCCUCACCGUCUACUAUAGCCCGGAGACCAUCGGCAGGCGAGUGGCUGUGGGACUCGGGUCCUGCCUCGCCAUCCUCAUCCUGGCAAUCUGUGGGCUCAAGCUCCAGCGACGUUGGAAGAGGACACAGAGCCAGCAGGGGCUUCAGGAGAAUUCCAGCGGCCAGAGCUUCUUUGUGAGGAAUAAAAAGGUUAGAAGGGCCCCCCUCUCUGAAGGCCCCCACUCCCUGGGAUGCUACAAUCCAAUGAUGGAAGAUGGCAUUAGCUACACCACCCUGCGCUUUCCCGAGAUGAACAUACCACGAACUGGAGAUGCAGAGUCCUCAGAGAUGCAGAGACCUCCCCCGGACUGCGAUGACACGGUCACUUAUUCAGCAUUGCACAAGCGCCAAGUGGGCGACUAUGAGAACGUCAUUCCAGAUUUUCCAGAAGAUGAGGGGAUUCAUUACUCAGAGCUGAUCCAGUUUGGGGUCGGGGAGCGGCCUCAGGCACAAGAAAAUGUGGACUAUGUGAUCCUCAAACAUUGACACUGGAUGGGCUGCAGCAGAGGCACUGGGGGCAGCGGGGGCCAGGGAAGUCCCCGAGUUUCCCCAGACACCGCCACAUGGCUUCCUCCUGCGCGCAUGUGCGCACACACACACACACACGCACACACACACACACACACUCACUGCGGAGAACCUUGUGCCUGGCUCAGAGCCAGUCUUUUUGGUGAGGGUAACCCCAAACCUCCAAAACUCCUGCCCCUGUUCUCUUCCACUCUCCUUGCUACCCAGAAAUCCAUCUAAAUACCUGCCCUGACAUGCACACCUCCCCCUGCCCCCACCACGGCCACUGGCCAUCUCCACCCCCAGCUGCUUGUGUCCCUCCUGGGAUCUGCUCGUCAUCAUUUUUCCUUCCCUUCUCCAUCUCUCUGGCCCUCUACCCCUGAUCUGACAUCCCCACUCACGAAUAUUAUGCCCAGUUUCUGCCUCUGAGGGAAAGCCCAGAAAAGGACAGAAACGAAGUAGAAAGGGGCCCAGUCCUGGCCUGGCUUCUCCUUUGGAAGUGAGGCAUUGCACGGGGAGACGUACGUAUCAGCGGCCCCUUGACUCUGGGGACUCCGGGUUUGAGAUGGACACACUGGUGUGGAUUAACCUGCCAGGGAGACAGAGCUCACAAUAAAAAUGGCUCAGAUGCCACUUCAAAGAA